GUCAGAAAUCGGAUAUCUACACUUCCCCGUCUCCCAAAAGAGCUUCCCUCCUUAGGCGUCCGGAGGUCUCUUGGAUUUUUCACUGCUAAUCCCAUCUGUCUUCACUAGACUCACUUCCCACAACUUGCUCCAGGAGGGGCCUAUGUGGACACUGAAGGCGACUGGGGCGGUUCCUCUUCUGAUGUAGUUAGCUCUCAGUUAGCUCACCGCCCAGUUCUCCUUGAUCUCUCCGGGCUGGACCGCCUCGUAAGCAGGAGGAGCAUAGAAGGAGGCGGGCUCCACAAGCUUGAUCUUCUGAAUCCCCUUGUCUCUGUAAACUUCCCCUGGAAGAAGCGAUGCACUGGCGAAGCCAUGUGAGGGGGGCUUUUGGUUCCAGAGAGACAGCCCGAGAGCCCCAGUGGGAACCAUCCGGAGACCCAGAAGAUCGAAUUCGCGGGACGGCGCGUUACCUUCCAACACCGCUGGGCCACCACUCUGAGAACCAGAAUCAGCGGUACUGGGGCUUCCCCACGGGACAGGAGCGCGUUCUUUGGAUUCCCCUGGUGCGGCGUGCACAACCUUCGGACGAAGAGUCCACGCCUGCCACCCAGGAGGAGGCCCAGGCGCAGGCAGGAGUGGCGGCCGCAGCCUCGUCGGAGGAGCCCGGUCACUGCGCUCCGCGGCCGCCACACGCGCCGCGAUCGGCCCUCUUCGAAGACUGGUCGCGGGAACCAGAGAGGUCUGACGAUGGGGACCUCUCGGAGUGUCGUCGCCCUGCUACUGAGCCUUGGCGGCCACCGGGCUCAGCCUGGAGGCUUCCUUGUGCAGCAUAGGCCGCCUGUCCGCCAAGAAGACCGCAGCCUGCCUGGGACGGCCGCCCUGGGCGCUCAGAAGCCAGGAGAUGUCCAACGAGGCCCUUGGGUUCCUGAUCCUCUGCCCAAGAACUGGGUUUCCGUAAUGCCUCUGCUCUGUUCCCAUGCCACUCAGGAGGCUGUGGCUGAGCAGCGCUUCGGACACAUUAUUCUCUUUAGUCUGUUCUCGGAAUAAAAUCCAACGCCAAGGCAAAA